ACAGCACCCUCCUGAAAACUGCAGCUUCCUUCUCACCUUGAAGAAUAAUCCUAGAAAACUCACAAAAUGUGUGAUGCUUUUGUAGGUACCUGGAAACUUGUCUCCAGUGAAAACUUUGAUGAUUAUAUGAAAGAAGUAGGAGUGGGCUUUGCCACCAGGAAAGUGGCUGGCAUGGCCAAACCUAACAUGAUCAUCAGUGUGAAUGGGGAUGUGAUCACCAUUAAAUCUGAAAGUACCUUUAAAAAUACUGAGAUUUCCUUCAUACUGGGCCAGGAAUUUGACGAAGUCACUGCAGAUGACAGGAAAGUCAAGAGCACCAUAACCUUAGAUGGGGGUGUCCUGGUACAUGUGCAGAAAUGGGAUGGAAAAUCAACCACCAUAAAGAGAAAACGAGAGGAUGAUAAACUGGUGGUGGAAUGCGUCAUGAAAGGCGUCACUUCCACGAGAGUUUAUGAGAGAGCAUAAGCCAAGGGACGUUGACCUGGACUGAAGUUCGCAUUGAACUCUACAACAUUCUGUGGGAUAUAUUGUUCAAAAAGAUAUUGUUGUUUUCCAUGAUUUAGCAAGCAACUAAUUUUCUCCCAAGCUGAUUUUAUUCAAUAUGGUUACGUUGGUUAAAUAAACUUUUUUUAGAUUUAGAAGGUGAUGUAAUGAUGUAUUCAUUGUGCUUAUGAUGUAUUCUUAGUCAUAACUGAGUGAAGGAAAUGGGAAAUUUGCAUUAUUUCUUUGUUCUGAUAUGAAUAAUAACAUAUUUCAUAAUAAUUCAAGGUAAAAAGGGAUAUCUAUGGAUUUCCCUAGGUAGGAGAUAACAAGUAUGUACCAUUACUGAAUAUUAAAUCCUUCUUUACCAUAGCUACAGUUAAGUAGGUGUAUCUCAGAAACCUAAGGUAGUUUUAAAUGUAGUGAAAUUG